CCUCUCGCCGCCGAGGGUCAGGAGCCCGGGAGCGCGACCCUCCCCCGGCCCGGCCUGGCCCGGCCUGGCCAGUCCCCGCGGUCUCUGCCCGGGCUGACGCCCAGGAAUGUGGUCGACGAGAAGCCCCAACAGCACGGCGUGGCCUCUCAGCCUCGGAAGUCUCCAAGGACCCCCAUGAAACACCUGCAUUUCCUGUCAUGAUUUUGAGGCUGAAAUCAUCUUCCUCCUCCCAGAACACCUAGGUGUUCUAGUCUGAAGCCAUCCUCACUCUCAACUCCCCUCCUUCGAGCCCUCACCCUGUGCCUGAAUUCUUCCUUCUUUGCUGGGACAGAUGGACAGGAGGAAGACAGGAAGUGGGGAACCCCUUCAACAACUCCUAUGGCAGAGGGGAGCCAUAGGAGAUGGGCCGGGAAAUGUAAAGACCAGCCCACGCAGGAAAAAAAGAGAACUUUUUAGCACAGUGUCAUCUGAAAAUGCAAGAGAAGAGAGGCUCUUGGUGGCAACAGAGGAGUGUGACUUCCAGCCUCAGGGCUAGCACCUGACCCCUGCUCUCCGUCCACAUCUGAAAAAUACCACUGGCCCUGAGAAUCCAUUGCAACUGAGGUUCUGCACCCCAACAGCUGCACUCAAGCUGCCAACUGAAGCAGAGAGCACUGCCCGCACUGCAGGGUUGUGCCUGUGUGCCCCGCUGCCUCCAGGGGUGGCUGCCUUCUGCCAGAGAAUGGACAGCUGACAUCCUGAGGACAUAGAGAGUUAGUAGGAAUGACUGUAGCCAAUGGCAAAUCCCAUGGAUGAAAAGCCACUCCCAACUCCACAAAGAUGAGCAUAGUGAAGGCUGCAGUUUAGUUGGUUCGUGGUUCCCCAGAAGGCUUUCAAACAUUCAGCAGUUGUCAUUCAGUGCCAGGCACCCAGUCUAAUGCUGAGUAUAGAGUUGUGAGCAAGACAAGCCUGAACGUGUGGAGCUUCCUGUCUGAGCCUGAUCCGGGGAUGGCCUCUGCCUCCACCACAAUGCAUACUACCACCAUUGCAGAGCCUGAUCCAGGGAUGUCUGGAUGGCCGGAUGGCAGAAUGGAGACCUCCACCCCCACCAUAAUGGACAUUGUCGUCAUUGCAGGUGUGAUUGCUGCUGUGGCCAUCGUCCUAGUCUCCCUCCUCUUCGUCAUGCUGCGCUACAUGUACCGGCACAAGGGCACGUACCACACCAAUGAGGCCAAGGGCACGGAGUUUGCUGAGAGUGCAGAUGCAGCCCUGCAGGGAGACCCUGCCCUCCAAGAUGCUGGUGAUAGCAGCAGAAAGGAGUACUUUAUUUGAGGGACAACAGACUUCACUUCCCUGAAUGCCUCCCCCAUCUCCAUCAGGAAAAAUACACCCCAUCGCCCAGCACCCCUGCUGAUACCACCAGACAGAGAGAGAGAGCACUUGAUUCUUCCCGAGAUAGCCACCUGGAAACACUAGGUGCCUGCCCAGGGAGGAACGGAGGAGGACUCGCGCUACAAGAGGCCACUCCCAGGGACCCAGGGAGGCGAUGGCCACCCCAGAGGCCACCUUUUGCUCCACGGAGGUGGGAGAAAAUCUGGGCACAUGGGGCCCCCUGGGCAGUGCAGGACAACAUCAGCUCACUGGCAGGAAAGUCCUUGUUGAGGGUGAGGGGGUGCUGGGGUACCCGGGGGCUGGGGAAGCAAGGAAAUAAGUCAUCUGUAUGCUGACUGGGGAUAAUGGCAUCAAAUGUCAGUCCUUGACAUUUGGGGGGAACAGCAGGUGCCAGAGCUAAAAGGUACCUUUGUCUGCCAUUGAUCCAGCUCAGAACGAUUGGAAAUAAAUUUGAAAUGUAACCGA